AUGCGCGUGGCGGGCAGGCGGCAGGAGGCGGGUGGGUCAAGGUAACUCUGGGCUACAGAGUCCUUGCUGGGGGUUCGGGGAGCGCUUGGACCCCGGCUUCUGGGACGCGUCAGAAUAUUAUCCAGCAAUGCAAAUGAACAAACUAUAACUACACACAGCUGCAUGGAUAAAUGUCAGAAACAUGACGUUGAGUGUGAGAAGCCAGAUGCAAACGAGGACUCACUGUGCAAUUCUGUGCAUGUACAGUGGCCAGGAGAAGGGAGCACUGGCUUUGCUUUCAUCAGGCCAAAGAUGCCUUUCUUUGGGAAUACGUUCAGUCCGAAGAAGACACCUCCUCGGAAGUCGGCAUCUCUCUCCAACCUGCAUUCUUUGGAUCGAUCAACCCGGGAGGUGGAGCUGGGCUUGGAAUACGGAUCCCCGACUAUGAACCUGGCAGGGCAAAGCCUGAAGUUUGAAAAUGGCCAGUGGAUAGCAGAGACAGGGGUUAGUGGCGGUGUGGACCGGAGGGAGGUUCAGCGCCUUCGCAGGCGGAACCAGCAGUUGGAGGAAGAGAACAAUCUCUUGCGGCUGAAAGUGGACAUCUUAUUAGACAUGCUUUCAGAGUCCACUGCUGAAUCCCACUUAAUGGAGAAGGAACUGGAUGAACUGAGGAUCAGCCGGAAGAGAAAAUGAAGACCCCAGAGACAUUUAUUGGGGAGUAGGAUGUGGCUGAGUGCUUUUUUUUUGGCCAGACUAGCGGAUUCAGUCCUGGAAGAGAGUAUCAUAUAAUGAGACCCACAGGCACUGGCACCCUUGGGUUGGCAAUAGAAGGUGACAUGGAAUGGAGAAAACCAAGAUUCCAGAUGGGGAUAGUAACUAGAAGGUGCUUCAGAUGCACUGCCUGCGGGUGCCAGUCUGAAAACCAGACCGCACAGAGGCCUGGGGCUGCUGAUGAGCUUUUUGGUGCUCUCCACACACAAGCUCGCAAACACACAUGUCCCAGAAUAGCUCUGUUGGGUUGUGUUGGGAGAAGCGGCUGGAGUUCAUUCUCUCACCCCCUUAUGUUGGUGUUUGGCGUGUGACAGCAGUUCUACAGAGCUCUGUGUUGGGGUCAUGGAUGAGCGGCUCUCUUGGCUCUUAAAGGCAGGCCUCUCUCUUCUUGCCUUUAAAGAAUCCUCCUUCCUCACACCUGGCCUCCUCUGGCUUCAGCUUCUCAGCAGCAAGCACCAGCCUUCCACAACAACACUAUAUUUUUAUGCUACUUUCCUGUUUGCACUACUACUUUUUUAUUAAACGAUGUUAAAUAA